AUAGCAGCUUAUAGUCGUUCAGAGAAACAUGUUCCACUGAGAAUGACUUGAGAGAGAGGAUUACAUCAUUAUGCCAGAAGGAAGAAGCCACUGUGCAUGCUCUAUCACCAGCCUCACCCUCCUGGUCAGCCUUACAAGAGUGACACUGGAUAUACUCCAGAAGUUGGACCCACCACAGCCUGCACACUGGACUUCUUGGCUUUUAUGAGCUAUUCAAGAGAUAUUUAGUCAUCACGUUGUGUCACAAUGGGAGUGACUCACAGAGCAAGGAGAGAACCUGAGGAUUCCUCACACAUGUAGUACUCAGAGCUCUACGGAAACCCAGGCACCUCGACCUCAAGAGGAUCAGCCUGGCCAGGGUGGCACAACUCUUCCUUCCCCGUGCACAGCAGGAAAGCUGCCAUCAGCUGAGCAAGUCCACCAACAGUUUCUGUGUCCCACUUCAUCUUUAAUAAGGAAAACAAACUCAGGAAGAAAAAGAAAAGCAGAAGUGAUCAAGGAGAGCGCUCGAGUUGCAAUAUUUUCCUUUGGCUGCUGACAGGCAGUUACUAUAAAGCAUUGUGCAUGGUGUAUGAAAGACAAAACUAGUUCUCCUUUCUUGGUUUCUUUUGAAUCUUUGUGAUAUGGUAGAGAAAGUUUGAUAAAGUGUUCUUGUGCCUGCUGUCGACUGAUAAUGUGUUCAUCUCUUUGCAGUUCUUCCUUCUCUUUCACACAGUUUAGAGUUCAGAGAGUUUUAGUUCUGGUCACUCUCUGGCAAGUGACCAUAGUUAUGACCUCUACUCUACACCAGAAAUAUCUUGACAAUUACAUGAGAUAAAUAUUACAUAAACACUUCCCAAAACUUUGUAAUGUUAUCAAAAUUGGAAGUGUGAAUAUUAUGUAUUAUUAUAAUUGCUAUCAUCCUUUUGCCCCAGCGAUUCAGAGGUCUCAAAGAUUAAUCCAAUUAUCACUAGAACUCUGGAGCUACAGUGGAGACUUCCUUCUUUCCUUCCUUUUUUCCUUCUUUGCUGUACAACAUUUACUAAACAUCAACAUAAUGCCAAGUAUCAUACAAGGAACUGGUAAUGUAGAGAAGUAUAUGCAGAGCCCAGAGUUGAGUGGGAAUACAGACUGCAGUGGUAGAACAGAAUGGUCUGGGUAUCAGUCCCGGAAUUGCCACUACAACUGUAGCUGGAGCCAAUUAAACAGAGCUUCUGAAUGUGUUUCCUCCUCUAUACAGUGAAGAUAAUUUUGUCGUAAGGUGUAAAUAAGAUAAAUAUUUAUAGAUCCUAGGAAACGGCCUACAACAUGUUAGGCACUCAAUGAACCAUAGCAGUUAUUAUCAUUCCUCCCUGACUUGGUCAACCAGGAACUUGAGAAUCAUAGAUUUGCUAGGAGGAUAUUUUGAAUUCUGUAGGGUCAGUUGGCCACCCACCAAAGGGUACCCCCAGAGGAGCUGGGGGUCAACAGCAUGGGGUAAACCUUGAGGGAGGGAACAGAUGGGAGGUGAUUGGAUGAAGAGAUUUGGGUGAGGACACAGAGCCAAACCAUAUCAGCCUCUUAUCCUCCUGAUGACAAAAAGACAUUUUAAAAUAUUUAUAUAGAGGGAAAUUAAUGCUUGCAGCAGCAGGAUAUGAGUAAUUUUUAUAAGUAACCCAACUUUUCCAUGAGGCCAUUAAAAAAAGAAACUCAUCAAUGUGAUACUACCAAGGAACCAAUGACUAAGUUUCCAGAAAAGUAGUUCUAGUGCUAUGAUAUUCUGGACUCCCAACACUAGGAAGUUCUAGAACAGUGGUUCUAAACUGGGGGAUAUUUUGUCCUCCAGGGGACAUUUGGCAUUAUCUGGAGACAUUUUUGGUUUUCACAACUUGGGGAGGGGUGCUACUGCUGACUAGAGAGUAGAGGCCAGAGAUGCCACUAAACAUGCUAAAUGCACAGGACUGACCCCACAACAAAUAAUUACCUGGCCCAAAAUAUCAAAAUUACUCAGUUAGAGGAAUCAAUGCCUAAAUAUGAGCAAUACAUAGAGCAGACUGCCUCAUAAAGUGAAAGUGAUUCACCCUGCCAUGAAGAUAACAAAGUUCUUACUGUAACGGCAGACAUUAGGUCACUUCACCCAGUACUCUCCAAGGUAGAUGUUGUAUUUCUACUUUACAGGUAGGAAAAUGGAGGCUAAGAAAAGUUAAUUUGUCCGAGGGCCCUCUGAUGAUAGUGAAACUGGGAUGGAACCUCUGCCUGCUUGCUUCUGAGGUCUGGGCUCCUAACUACUGCUCUACUGCCUCGAGCCAAGAGAUUUACGCCCUAUUAAGCAAUUUGUUGUGCGAUAAAUUGGAAGACACAGCAGAUAAGCAAACAACUCAAGCAACCAGGACACCAUCUUCUUGUAUUAUACAAGAAAGGAGUGUACCUAUCACACACAGGGGGAAAAAUGCUCUUUUGGGUGCUAGGCCUCCUAAUCCUCUGUGGUUUUCUGUGGACUCGUAAAGGAAAACUAAAGAUUGAAGACAUCACUGAUAAGUACAUUUUUAUCACUGGAUGUGACUCGGGCUUUGGAAACUUGGCAGCCAGAACUUUUGAUAAAAAGGGAUUUCAUGUAAUCGCUGCCUGUCUGACUGAAUCAGGAUCAACAGCUUUAAAGGCAGAAACCUCAGAGAGACUUCGUACUGUGCUUCUGGAUGUGACCGACCCAGAGAAUGUCAAGAGGACUGCCCAGUGGGUGAAGAACCAAGUUGGGGAGAAAGGUCUCUGGGGUCUGAUCAAUAAUGCUGGUGUUCCCGGCGUGCUGGCUCCCACUGACUGGCUGACACUAGAGGACUACAGAGAACCUAUUGAAGUGAACCUGUUUGGACUCAUCAGUGUGACACUAAAUAUGCUUCCUUUGGUCAAGAAAGCUCAAGGGAGAGUUAUUAAUGUCUCCAGUGUUGGAGGUCGCCUUGCAAUCGUUGGAGGGGGCUAUACUCCAUCCAAAUAUGCAGUGGAAGGUUUCAAUGACAGCUUAAGACGGGACAUGAAAGCUUUUGGUGUGCACGUCUCAUGCAUUGAACCAGGAUUGUUCAAAACAAACUUGGCAGAUCCAGUAAAGGUAAUUGAAAAAAAACUCGCCAUUUGGGAGCAGCUGUCUCCAGACAUCAAACAACAAUAUGGAGAAGGUUACAUUGAAAAAAGUCUAGACAAACUGAAAGGCAAUAAAUCCUAUGUGAACAUGGACCUCUCUCCGGUGGUAGAGUGCAUGGACCACGCUCUAACAAGUCUCUUCCCUAAGACUCAUUAUGCCGCUGGAAAAGAUGCCAAAAUUUUCUGGAUACCUCUGUCUCACAUGCCAGCAGCUUUGCAAGACUUUUUAUUGUUGAAACAGAAAGCAGAGCUGGCUAAUCCCAAGGCAGUGUGACUCAGCUAACCACAAAUGUCUCCUCCAGGCUAUGAAAUUGGCCGAUUUCAAGAACACAUCUCCUUUUCAACCCCAUUCCUUAUCUGCUCCAACCUGGACUCAUUUAGAUCGUGCUUAUUUGGAUUGCAAAAGGGAGUCCCACCAUCGCUGGUGGUAUCCCAGGGUCCCUGCUCAAGUUUUCUUUGAAAAGGAGGGCUGGAAUGGUACAUCACAUAGGCAAGUCCUGCCCUGUAUUUAGGCUUUGCCUGCUUGGUGUGAUGUAAGGGAAAUUGAAAGACUUGCCCAUUCAAAAUGAUCUUUACCGUGGCCUGCCCCAUGCUUAUGGUCCCCAGCAUUUACAGUAACUUGUGAAUGUUAAGUAUCAUCUCUUAUCUAAAUAUUAAAAGAUAAGUCAAACAUU